AGGACGGUAGAAGUCGUGGUUUGUGCGCGGCCAGGCGCUGGAGCCUCCGCUGCCGGGAGCAGUAAGUGUGUGACGUCGGGGUAGAAGGGAGUGACCCAAAUUCCAAAAGCUCUUUGGGAUGCUGCGAUGUCGCGGCCGGCCCCGCGCUCGGGUUUUCCCUCCUAGACAAAAGUCUGCCGGCUCCCGGUCGCGCCGGGUCGGGGAUCCGGAAGGUGAAGGCCGCCAGGCCCCACCUGCGGGGCGCCCCUGCUGGACCUGGCCGUCGGGCGCCGUCAACCCGUUGAGCAGCGUGUUCCGGCUGGCACGUGGCCCGGGCGGGGCCCAGGAUUGGUUCAAGCCUACGGUGUUGGUCCCCGGAGAGUCUAGGGAGACAAGCAAUCCCCUGGAAUGGUGGGGGAAGCGAUGACAGCCCCUGGUCCUCAUCCGCAGCUCUGGGGGAAGUCGGGGGGUGGGGAGGGCGGGUGUUGCUCCCUGAGUGUUGGGGGAAGGGUAUGGGGAGAGGACCCUGAACUAGCCCCCAGGUUACCCAGGAGGAGCUGAGGCCCAGAGAGGUUCAGCGACUCGCCCAGGGUUGCACAGCGAGCACAGGCACCGACGUCGCCCUCCGAGGCCUGGGCUUCCAGCAGGGAGAGACCCGGACACCUGUCAUCGCUUCUCGGUGGAUCCCUGAAAUAUCAGACCUUCCAGCUGCCUCUCAUGUACUUGUCUGUUGGGGGCUUGUGUUGAUCAGGAGUGAAUUCACAGUCUACCAUGAAUUGGAAGGUUCUUGAGCACGUGCCCCUGCUGCUGUAUAUCUUGGCAGCAAAAACAUUAAUUCUCUGCCUGACAUUUGCUGGGGUGAAAAUGUAUCAAAGAAAAAGGUUGGAGGCAAAACAACAAAAACUGGAGGCUGAAAGGAAGAAGCAAUCAGAGAAAAAAGAUAACUGAAGAUUCUGCCAUGUAAAUGUCAGCUUGAGUGGACUCCAGCUGAGAAGAAAGAGAAGAAAGACUUAAUUAUUGAAUAAUUUGUCAGAGGAUAAACUCCCAACCUAGACCUUUCACUUAAAAUAGUGUGAAUUUGUAUAUGUUUUUAAAAGAACCAGUACUGGCCGGGUAUGCUGGCUUUUACCUGAAAUCCCAGCACUUUGGGAGGCCGAGGCGAGUGGAUCGCCUGAGAUCGGGAGUUUGAGACCAGCCUGGCCAACAUGGUAAAAUCCUGUCUCUACUAAAAAUAUAAAAAUUAGCCAGGUGUAGUGGCGCGCGUCUGUAAUCCCAGCUACUCGGGAGGCUGAGGCAGGAGAAUUGCUUGAAUCCGGGAGGUGGAGGUUGCAGUGAGCCUAGGUCGUGCCACUGCCCUCCAGCCUGGGUGACAGAGCGACUGCGUCUCCAAAAAAAAAAAGGUAAAAUUAAAAUUAAAAAAAAUAAUAAUAACCAGUAUUUUGUUUACUAAAAUAAAAUGCCUUUGUAAAAAAA